GCAGUCAAAUCCCGCUCUCCGCCCGCCGCCCGCGGAAGUCUCACCGCGCAGCAGCACCCCCAGCCCGGGCGGUUCCGGGGACCGAAGGGCGCGGCACGUAGGGGGCCCGUAGGAUCCAAACUGCGGAGGAGAAGCAGGAGGAGGGAGGAGGAAGAAGACAAAGGAGCAGCUUCUAGUUGCAGCUCAAGACCCGCGAGUUCACCCUCCGCGCCAAGCACCCAACUCCCGGCUCUGCCUACAGUCACCCACAGACCUAAUGAUCGACUAAGCGCCGUAAUGGCCCGAGAUGACACCAGGAGACUCCCUUGCUGUGCGCCUCCGGAAGACGCGGAACGUAGCCCCUUUCUCACACUCCUGGGACACAAAAAUACCCGACAACUCAAAGUCGCCAAACCACAUCUUUUCAUGCUUUGAAGACUUCUGCCCAAGGCUGUGGCAGGAGUAUGUCCAACUGUGAUUUGGGAUUCUUUUUAAACAUCGAAUCAAAGGGAAGAGGGGAGGGAUUCGCAACUAAAUGGUAGUUGUUUUCAAGCAAGUCUUUACGUAGCCCCAAACCUACUCUAGUAUUCGGUGAUUCAGCCCCAAAACAUCUCUGCCUGCCUUUAUGUUCGGAUCUCACUCCAUUAUUUGUCAGCACCAAGUACUAAACCCACAAAGCGAUCGCUGUACGGGACACCAAACCCAUACCUGCCCGUCCCCUACCUUCCAGGCAACCAGUGUCAAUCUCCUCACUAUACAUAAUUCCCAACAUCCCUGCCCGAAGUGAGGAGAACGGUAAUUUAAAUAAUACAGCGGGGGAGGAGAGGACACACUGUUUUUGAAAGACUGUAAGCAUUCUGCUGUUCCACUCUGCGUCCUUACACUUGCUGAGCACUGACACCAAAUUUAAAUGGCGUUCCUUCAAAACUGAUGUAAUUGUAAAGAGCUGUAAAGGGCAAUGACCUCAAGUGGAUGUUUUUUCCCAGGUACCCUACAAGGUUUGCACAAAGCAAGAAAGCAUCAUGUAACCGAAAUGCUGAAAAGUAUAGAUGCUGCAAAACCUCAUUCUGAGACUGAGAACUAUGAAUAGUCAGUGUAUUUCCUUCUGCGGUGCAGAAAAAGAACAACCAAAAAGAAAGCAACAAGGGGAGAUGUUAUUUAUUUUAAUGACACCAAAACUACCAAUCCUAGCAAUUUAAUAAAUUAAAAUCAUAGUCCUUUAAAUGUAUUUAAUGGUUCAAGUUUGUGUAUUUGGUGUUAACUCUCUGGUAAAGUUUAUGGAAAACAGUGAAGUACGUUAAUUGAGCAAAUUUUAUAUUAAAAAAGGAAUAACACAUUUUAAAAUGUUUUUAUAUACCCACAAUAUUUGUGUUUCUUAGCUUGGUUCCUACUAUUACAUAAUACAAUGCAUUUCUUAUUUUUUAAAGAGCAAAAAGUGUUGUCACUUCUGGAUCACUUUAUGGUAAUUCCUAGGUAUACUUCUAAGCAAACAAACAUAUCUAUUUAUAAUUUUAUUCAACUCACAAGUAAGAGAUAUUUAAAAAAAACAAAUUGAAAGUUUUUUUUUUCUUCCUGAUGCAAAACUUAACAAACUCCAAUUAAAUUCAAUAUUGGUCUGCCAGGGAAACGACCAUAAAAUUUACAGAAAUUCUCCCAAAGAUGCCUUUCAAUUCUUCUCCUGACUUUAGUUCUAACUAUACCAUUUUUUUAUAAUUCCUCUAUAAAAAUCGAAUCAAAUCAAAGACGACGAGGAAAGAAAAAUAUUUCUAGAGUGAUCUUAAUUAACUGAUCAUUUCAGCAAAGAGCAUUAGCAAUGAAGAAGCGGCGAAACUGUAGGGAGAAAAAAAAGGAUGCAUUUUGUUCUUCGUGUUUAUAAUCCUUCCUAGAGAACAGAAACUACGAGCAUGAUUUAUGGAACUGCAUUAUCUUGGAUUUUCUCCGCAGAUUUGACUCAACUUAGUAUCAGUGUUCUGUUAAAGCGCUGGAAUAAGUGGAUACAUCUGCAGAGGUAAGAAACGUGGUUUGGGUCGGAUGAGCCUCCUUGUUGCUGGAGGGUGCUUCGAGGACCAGGCUUAGGAGAGAAGGGGUUAAGUCAGACCCUGUCUUUAGCGGCGCAACGUGCCCAGUUUUGUCUGUUAAAGUCAACGUCGCCCAACUGGAGCCAGCCAAUGGACGGCCGGGAGCGCCCGGGACAGCCCAGUGGAGGGGUGUGGCCUCAGGCUGUCACUCAGCAGUGAGGAAUGACACCCGGGCGGGAGGGGGGUGGUACAGUGGAACGCAAGGGAAGGAAAGAGAAAAGAAACAGAUAAAACCAGGGCAGGGGGUAAAAAAGUUCCCCGCGCCUCUCGGAAUCCAGCGGCCGCGGCCGCGGCUACCGCCGCCGCCGCCGGGGGUGGGCUCCGGAAGAGCCUGCCCAGCAGGGAAGGGGAGGACGGGCCAGGAGCGAAAUCCUGCAGGCGAGGAAGGGACAGACGCGCAAAGAAAAAGUGACUCGGGCUGUGCGCCCCGGCGGCGCUCGGGAGGGGACUGCUGCCACGGAGGGGCCCCCGCCAAUCCUCCUUCACGUCCCCCGAGGGGGCAGACCCCAGCCCGCCCCUAAGGGCGAGAAGCGAUGAGAUAAUCCAGCUGAGCUGCGAAAGGAGAGCGUCUGGCUCUGGAUUCGGGGGGAGGGGGUCUCCGGGCGGGGUGGGCCUCUAAGGUGGGGGCGAGGGUCGGCGCUGAUCCUGGGACGGAGUGGGGCGGGAGCUGCUGGGCCGCGCAGCAGUGGGCGGCGGCGGCCUCGCACACCCAGCUCACUCGCGCUGCGGCCGCCGGCGCUCUCUGUCCCGCUCGGAGCUGCUCGGCGCCCCAGCUGCCCGCCCCGCCGGCCGCUCCUGCCCGCGGCGCAGAUGGCUGUGCGCGGCGCCAACACCUUGACGUCCUUCUCCAUCCAGGCGAUCCUCAACAAGAAAGAGGAGCGCGGCGGGCUGGCCGCGCCAGAGGGGCGCCCGGCGCCCGGGGGCACAGCGGCAUCGGUGGCCGCGGCUCCCGCUGUCUGCUGUUGGCGGCUCUUUGGGGAGAGGGACGCGGGCGCGUUGGGGGGCGCCGAGGACUCUCUGCUGGCGUCUCCUGCCGGUACCAGAACAGCUGCGGGGCGGACUGCGGAGAGCCCGGAAGGCUGGGACUCGGACUCCGCGCUCAGCGAGGAGAACGAGAGCAGGCGGCGCUGCGCGGACGCGCGGGGGGCCAGCGGGGCCGGCCUUGCGGGGGGAUCCUUGAGCCUCGGCCAGCCGGUCUGUGAGCUGGCCGCUUCCAAAGACCUAGAGGAGGAAGCCGCGGGCCGGAGCGACAGCGAGAUGUCCGCCAGCGUCUCAGGCGACCGCAGCCCAAGGACCGAGGACGACGGUGUUGGCCCCAGAGGUGCACACGUGUCCGCGCUGUGCAGCGGGGCCGGCGGCGGGGGCGGCAGCGGGCCGGCAGGCGUCGCGGAGGAGGAGGAGGAGCCGGCGGCGCCCAAGCCACGCAAGAAGCGCUCGCGGGCCGCUUUCUCCCACGCGCAGGUCUUCGAGCUGGAGCGCCGCUUUAACCACCAGCGCUACCUGUCCGGGCCCGAGCGCGCAGACCUGGCCGCGUCGCUGAAGCUCACCGAGACGCAGGUGAAAAUCUGGUUCCAGAACCGUCGCUACAAGACAAAGCGCCGGCAGAUGGCAGCCGACCUGCUGGCCUCGGCGCCCGCCGCCAAGAAGGUGGCCGUAAAGGUGCUGGUGCGCGACGACCAGAGACAAUACCUGCCCGGCGAAGUGCUGCGGCCACCCUCGCUUCUGCCACUGCAGCCCUCCUACUAUUACCCGUACUACUGCCUCCCAGGCUGGGCGCUCUCCACCUGCGCAGCUGCCGCAGGCACCCAGUGAACCCGCUUGGGCUGAGGCAGCGAGUGAUUCCCGCGCUCCGGCUCCGGACCGGCGCUGACAGCUGUAGGCUGUAGCCUGCACGGGGCGCCCCGCCAAGGAGGCACCUGGAGGUGAAACCCAGCUCCAGCUCCCGUUAGCCAGGACUUGUCCCCUGGCAGCUGGGCUGAGUCUGCCCUGAGGGGGCGCCUUUUUCUAAUUUGAACAGAGGCACCCUAUGGCCUAGGGGCCCUGAUCGCCCACCUGCCUGGAAGCCCCUGGGCUCUAUUUAUUAUCAUGACAAUGUUGGAAUUAAAUUUUGAUUCGAAUAUGUCUGCCUGGGGGUGGGGUUUUCCCUGAGCGGCAACUCCUGGAGACCACAUAGCCUGAAUCCUCAGAAUUUCAGGCCUGCUGGGAGCUUUCUGCACUAGGCCACACUAGUUCAUGGUAUCCAUGCUACCAAUCUAUGUGUAUCUACAUAUCUUUUAUUUUUGGAAAUUGCAUUUGUAACCAAGGGGUGCGAAACCCUGGCAGUCCCAGGCAGCACCAGGCCAGGGGUUGAUUUGAAACGUGAAGGAUUGGGUUUUCAGGCCCUCUGCUCCACCCCUCCUGUGUGUCAGAGCUAGGGUGGGGGUGCCCGAUUCGGGUGCUGAAUGUAAGGAGGGGAGCCUCCAAGUGUGGUGCAAGCCGGGGGUCUCCACAUCUUCCUUCUCUGAAGUCCAGGUACCUGCACAAGCAGGAAGCGCCUGGGAGUCCCGGAAGGAGGAGAGCGCACACCCAGGCAGCCCUCUGCGGAAACUUUCCUUGGUUUCUUUUUAUUUGUGUAAAGGAGGUUAAGACGUGUCGCACUUUUCAGUUGUUUGUAUUCAAAUGACGAUUAUUUUUCUACUCAAUGUGAAUAUCCCUGGCCAGCCUUUCCACGGCGCCCACCGCAGUGCCGCUGCCUGGCCCUCAGUGUCUACCUUCUGCCCUCUGCGACUCCAGUGCUCUGGCCCGGGACUCCCCUAUCCGCCCCUCACUUACCCUUAAACAGGUGAUCCCACCUGUCUUGUCAACCUCGCCGCUUUUCGCCUCCUUAAUGGCACUGUGCACUCAACUAGAGUAUUAACUGUAAAAAGAUUUGUGAAGUUUGGAAGCUCUAUUCGCUGUAUUUUUUCUUUAAUUUAUAAACUUUUAGUUUAACAUGC